GCGUUGAGGCUGCGGUCAUGGAGGGAGCAGGAGCUGGAUCCGGCUUCCGGAAGGAGCUGGUGAGCAGGCUGCUGCACCUGCACUUCAAGGAUGACAAGACCAAAGUGAGCGGGGACGCGCUGCAGCUCAUGGUGGAGUUGCUGAAGGUCUUCGUUGUGGGUGAGCCCAGGGCCCACGCUCCCUCCGGGCACAGCAUCCGGAAUUUUGCGUUUUUCCAGCGGGAAAACCAAGACGUGUUUUCCCGUUUCCCACAAGGGCCUAAACUUGGGUCUCCUGAGCCUGUUUGUCAGAAGCAGCAGUCCGCGGCGUGCGGCAGGCCCAGGCAGAAGACGCGCUCCGUGUGGACGUGGACCAGCUGGAGAAGGUGCUUCCGCAGCUGCUCCUGGACUUCUAGGGAUCUCAGCCGUGGCUGAGGCCACCCCCAGAGGAGCCCCUGGUCCACAGAAGCAGGCCUUGUGUUUCCAGCGGCCUCUGAUAAGAGGCAGGGAAGGACCUGAAGGAUUUGGAGUUGAUUCAAACAAGAUCUCUGGGAGUCUCCAGCCUGUGCAGAAGGGGCAGGACUGCAGUGCACUGCGGGCCUUGGAGUGUCCAGUGGGGACACUGGUGUGGGAAGGGGCAGCACCUGGGGAGUCCCUGCCUCUCCUCCCUGGGACAAUAGUGUGCAUGCCACCCGGGGUCCUACAGGCAGGUGCUGGGAAAGGCCUGGCCAGCAGGUAGCCUGUGUGUUUGACAAACAGCAGCUGGCAGCGCUGCCUCCUGCCCACAUUCCUGCCACCCGACAUCAAAGCUGGCGUGUGACCUUUCCAGCCAUGCGAUAUUCCCCUUGGAAGAUGCUUCCCCAGGCUAUAAAUUUGUUCUCACAAAGCAACAUCAAUAAAUCAAAACUGUCUCUCCCA